ACUUGUGACGUCGCGGACGCCCGGCUCGGGCAGGCGUGGGGGGCCCGCGCGUCCCGGGAGCCCCGAGGCGGCAGCGCGCGUUUCCACGCCGCGGUCCCGCGGGAAAGCCGGGGGCGGCGGCCUGGCUGAGGCCAAGCUCGGAUCCGGUGCCGAGCCAAGCGGGGCCGUGCGUCGCCGGGGCUUCGCCUUCGCUCGCGUGACCUCCGCCGUCCUCCCCAACCCUCGUCCUCUGGCCGCGCCUGCGGCCGCACGCCCAGCGCCCCUCGCCUAACCUCGCGCCCGGGCCGCGCCUCCUCCUCCUCCUGCUCCCCGCCGCUUCCGUUUCUCGAGGGAAAGGCUGCUGCCUCCUGCUCUGUCCUCAUCCCCGGCUUAGGUAACACGUUUUCCUCCUUACGACACCCACCACAGGGUCCCCGCGCCGCUGCCCCUCCUCCUUGGAUCUGGGGCCCGGGCUGGUGAGCGGCGCGCGCCGUCGCCUCUCCGCGGGUAGUCCUUCAGAGCUUACAUCAUGUGGCCGAGUUUAUAUACCUGAUUGGCAAAACAGAGCCUAAGAACCAGCUCUCCUGUAUCCCAAGCAAGGCUCUUUCUACCGCACACCCUGCAGGCCCAUCCAGGCCCAUCCAGACAAUAAACACUGACGGCCCAGAGGGUGGGUGCCAAUUCCACCAGCAGCUGCAACUGAAAAGCAAGGUUCAGAAAUGUCAGAUAUCCUCCGGGAGCUGCUCUGUGUCUCUGAGAAGGCUGCUAACAUUGCCCGGGCGUGCAGACAGCAGGAAGCCCUCUUCCAGCUGCUGAUCGAAGAAAAGAAAGAGGGAGAAAAGAACAAGAAGUUUGCAGUUGACUUCAAGACGCUGGCUGAUGUACUGGUACAGGAAGUUAUAAAACAGAAUAUGGAGAACAAGUUUCCAGGCUUGGAAAAAAAUAUUUUUGGAGAAGAAUCCAAUGAGUUUACUAAUGACUGGGGGGAAAAGAUUACCUUGAGGUUGUGUUCAACAGAGGAGGAAACAGCAGAGCUUCUUAGCAAAGUCCUCAAUGGUAACAAGGUGGCAUCUGAAGCAUUAGCCAGGGUUGUUCAUCAGGAUGUUGCCUUUACUGACCCAACUCUGGAUUCCACAGAGAUCAAUGUUCCACAGGACAUUUUGGGAAUUUGGGUGGACCCCAUAGAUUCAACUUAUCAGUAUAUAAAAGGUUCUGCUGACAUUAAAUCCAACCAGGGAAUCUUCCCCUGUGGACUUCAGUGUGUCACCAUUUUAAUUGGUGUCUAUGACAUACAGACAGGGGUUCCCCUGAUGGGAGUCAUCAAUCAACCUUUUGUGUCACGAGAUCCAAACACCCUCAGGUGGAAAGGACAGUGCUAUUGGGGCCUUUCUUACAUGGGGACCAACAUGCAUUCACUACAGCUCACCAUCUCUAGAAGAAACGGCAGUGAAACACACACUGGAAACACCGGCUCUGAGGCAGCAUUCUCCCCCAGUUUUUCAGCCGUAAUUAGUACAAGUGAAAAGGAGACUAUCAAAGCUGCAUUGUCACGUGUGUGUGGAGAUCGCAUAUUUGGGGCAGCUGGGGCUGGUUAUAAGAGCCUAUGUGUUGUCCAAGGCCUCGUUGACAUUUACAUCUUUUCAGAAGAUACCACAUUCAAAUGGGACUCUUGUGCUGCUCAUGCCAUACUGAGGGCCAUGGGUGGGGGAAUAGUAGACUUGAAAGAAUGCUUAGAAAGAAAUCCAGAAACAGGGCUUGAUUUGCCACAGUUGGUGUACCACGUGGAAAAUGAGGGUGCUGCUGGGGUGGAUCGGUGGGCCAACAAGGGAGGACUCAUUGCAUACAGAUCCAGGAAGCGGCUGGAGACAUUCCUGAGCCUCCUGGUCCAAAACCUGGCACCUGCAGAGACGCAUACCUAGAGGAACUCUAACCCCGGUGUACCUGUAUAAACUGAACUGUGAAACUGUUUCGGUUAUCUCUGUCUUUUGAGGAUGGCUUUGUCCUGUUGCUGGUUAACAUUCACCUUCCUCUUUUGAGGAGUAUUUUUCCAUUAUGUAUUCAUAAUAAUGUUAAUUUCAAUAAAUGACAUUCAUGCAGCAAUUAUAUUGGUGUAUGAAAUUCUUACAGUGAAUAUUGUGCUGUUAGUGCUGCUUGAAACAUUUCAAUAAAAUAUUGACCAGGA